CGGACGGAGGGAAAGCACUGAGAACAGGAAGCUGCUUCACCCGAGAGUUCCUUGGUGCCCUUUCCGUAUUUCCAGCAGUUUGCUGAGAAGAAGACUUUUUGAAGAUCACGAUGGCCCUUCAUUUCUUGUUUGAUUCUUCUGGAUAAAGCAGCAUGAUAACCUGAAAGGAAAGCAUAAACAUCUGGAGCAGUUCCAAAGGCAUCUGGGGAGAGUCAGCACUGGAGGCUUGAAUAAAAGUGUUUACUUCUUCUUAUUCUCCAAAUCUCAAUGAAAUAAUAAUUUAAAAAAAAAACUAGAAAAAAAACAGAUCCAAUGUAGCACCGACUGUCAUUGGGAUCAGGUAUGAGUUGCCUGUUGUUGACAGAUCAUGGGAAACAAUAAGAAUUUUGUAGAAAAUACAAAACUAGGAAAAGAGAUUAGUGGUAAAAUAUAAAAGAGCAGGGUUUUAUAUAUUUUAAAAAUAAGUUUCUCUUACAACUGUUGGCAAAGCCCUAUAGACAAAGUUGGCGCUGGAAGAUGGUGCAGGUAGAAGGCCACAAGCAAAGGAAUUCAAUAUGGGGCUGUAGAAGCUCAGAGGCCACCUGUCAUCUGGGACAAAGCUGAAAGGAGUGCUCUAUGAAAUGGAGAUUCCAACACAGAAGGACGAGGGCAAUGCCCAGGAAACUUACAACUUGGACAAGACAAAGAUGCACCCCCAGAUGCAGAAAGCAGCUCGGCAGAGCCCAUCCUGACCCACAUCCCUCAUCCUGUCCUCCACAAAAUCCGUGGAGGCAGGGCUUCUGGACCCAGAAUCUGUAUUCACUGCUUUUCAAUAUAUGACUCCUCUUUCAGUGGUACAAAGAUUUCCUGUGGUAAACCAUCUAGUAUAAACACUCAAAUAAUCACUUCAAUCCUUAGACUAUCUAAUUCAAGUGCCACUAAAGUAUGCCUAAAACUCUCAUAGGAAACUGAUGACUGUAAGUUUAUUUCUUAAUAAAAAUGUAUUUUGCACAUAUAUAUAUAUACACACACUAUCUAUCUAUCAUCUAUCUAUCUAUCUAUCUAUCUAUCUAUCUAUCUAUCCUCUAUCUAUCUAUCUAUCAUCUAUCUAUCACCUAUCUAUCAUCUAUCUAUCUCAGGAUAGAGUAAAUAACAGAAAAACCUUAAAAAGUUACUUAUAAGAGCCUGUGAGAAAAAGCAUCCAACCCCAUUUAGCCCCUCAAUGUUGCCAGCAGGCUAUUCCCACCCUCCCAGGCAGCUGUGUCUAAGCAUAUAGACCUUCCUCUUUAUGCUCCACACCUCAUGGUCCCAAGAGGGCUACUUCACCUCCCUUUCUAUGUCUGCUUCAGGAAGGAAAGAAAGGAGAAAUAAGGCUUAGGGCUAGAAUCAGGAAAUAAAGGCUUUCCCAGAAACCUCCACACUUGUGCUUAGGUUGUAUUAGACAGAACUGUGUCACAUAGACACUGCUACUUGUAAGAGACACUGGGAAACCAUGUCUAGCACUUACAGCCUCGAAUGUUCCUGCUGUCCUACAUUCAAAGACAUUACUCUGUACAUAUUAACCUUCACUAUUCAGAUGAACUACAACUGGAACUGGAUCUAGGAUAUAGGGAAAUGAAGGAAAGGGGGCGUUGGAAUCCAGUAGACAUGGGUUGGAACCCAAACUCCAGCAAUUGACAGCUGUAUGCAUGGACAUAUUUAUUGUUUCUCCUUAAAAAGAUUUCCUUUUUAUUUAAAGGACUUGAAAUGCCUUUUAGUUGUGCCUGUAAAGACUGUGAAUCUUGCAUUUGCCUGUGAUCCUUAGCAGUAGGGUAAGCCCACAUCUGGCAUAUGUGCUGGCCAAAAUUACCCUGAAUAAGUGCAUGACAACUCUCAAUCUGUUUCUUCUUUCUGUAAAAUGGGAAAGCGGGCAUUGUACUGGACAGUUUUAAGGACUCUAUAAAACCAUGUAGGCAACAUAAAAAAUCAAAAUAUCCCUGGACACUUUGGGAGGCCAAGGUGGGUGCAUCACCUGAGGUCAGGAGUUUCAGACCAGCCUGUCCAACAUGGUGAAACCCAGUCUCUAAUAAAAAUACAAAAAUUAGCCAGGUGUGGUGGUGCACACCUGUAAUCCCAGCUACUUCAGAGGCUGAGGCAGGAGAAUUGCUUGAACCUGGGAGGUGGAGGUUGCAGUGAGCUGAGAUCACACCAUUGCACUCCAGCCUGGCGACAAGAGCCAAAUUCUGUUAAAAAAAAAAAAAAAAAACAAAAAACAAAAACAAAGAAAUCCCUGGAAAUUUACAUUUUUAACGACCAAUUACUUUGGAGUACAGCCUUGCACAUGGAUUGUUUUUACAAGGACUGUCAACCCACAAAAAUGUUUUCAAACCUCAGUUUUGAGAGGCCUCUCUCAAACUGCGUGUUUUAAUGAAAACUCAUUUAAAAGCAUUGAUUGCAUCUGACCAUCUCAUAGUCUUGGUCAGGUAUUUUUUGAAGAAUUACACAUUGCUUGGCAUUUGACCAAUGCUAAGUGGGCCUACUGACAUCACCAGCAAUCUAGAAAUUAGAAUUAUUUGAUUCCAUAGUUAUGUUUGUAACUAAGAGAUUGUUAUUCUUUUAUUUCAAAGCUACCCUAAUGUCCUGCAUGUCUCCAGUUUAUCUGAUGGAGCUGAACUAAUCUGAGUAUAUUAUGAACACAAGCAAAAAUUGUGCCAUCCUUCAUCAACAAAGAUACAGAAACCAUAAAUAUGAUGUCAGAAUUUGUUGCUAAUUUGCCACAGGAGCUGAAGUUAACCCUGUCUGAGAUGCAGCCAGCAUUACCACAGCUACAACAACAUGUACCUGUAUUAAAAGAUUCCAGUCUUCUCUUUGAAGAAUUUAAGAAACUUAUUCGCAAUAGACAAAGUGAAGCCGCAGACAGCAGUCCUUCAGAAUUAAAAUACUUAGGCUUGGAUACUCAUUCUCGAAAAAAGAGACAACUCUACAGUGCAUUGGCUAAUAAAUGUUGCCAUGUUGGUUGUACCAAAAGAUCUCUUGCUAGAUUUUGCUGAGAUGAAGCUAAUUGUGCACAUCUCGUAUAAUAUUCACACAUAUUCUUAAUGACAUUUCACUGAUGCUUCUAUCAGGUCCCAUCAAUUCUUAGAAUAUCUAAGAAUCUUUGUUAGAUAUUAGGUCCCAUCAAUUCUUAGAAUAUCUAAACAUCUUUGUUGAUGUUUAGAUUUUUUUAUUUGAUGUGUAAGAAAAUGUUCUUUGUGUGAUUAAAUGACACAUUUUUUUGCUGAAAA